AUGAACCCUGAAAACUGGACUCAGGUAACAAGCUUUGUCCUUCUGGGUUUCCCCAGUAGCCACCUCAUACAGUUCCUGGUGUUCCUGGGGUUAAUGGUGACCUACAUUGUAACAGCCACAGGCAAGCUGCUAAUUAUUGUGCUCAGCUGGAUAGACCAACGCCUGCACAUACAGAUGUACUUCUUCCUGCGGAAUUUCUCCUUCCUGGAGCUGUUGCUGGUAACUGUUGUGGUUCCCAAGAUGCUUGUCGUCAUCCUCACGGGGGAUCACACCAUCUCAUUUGUCAGCUGCAUCAUCCAGUCCUACCUCUACUUCUUUCUAGGCACCACUGACUUCUUCCUCUUGGCCGUCAUGUCUCUGGAUCGUUACCUGGCAAUCUGCCGACCACUCCGCUAUGAGACCCUGAUGAAUGGCCAUGUCUGUUCCCAACUAGUGCUGGCCUCCUGGCUAGCUGGAUUCCUCUGGGUCCUUUGCCCCACUGUCCUCAUGGCCAGCCUGCCUUUCUGUGGCCCCAAUGGUAUUGACCACUUCUUUCGUGACAGUUGGCCCUUGCUCAGGCUUUCUUGUGGGGACACCCACCUGCUGAAACUGGUGGCUUUCAUGCUCUCUACGUUGGUGUUACUGGGCUCACUGGCUCUGACCUCAGUUUCCUAUGCCUGCAUUCUUGCCACUGUUCUCAGGGCCCCUACAGCUGCUGAGCGAAGGAAAGCGUUUUCCACUUGCGCCUCGCAUCUUACAGUGGUGGUCAUCAUCUAUGGCAGUUCCAUCUUUCUCUACAUUCGUAUGUCAGAGGCUCAGUCCAAACUGCUCAACAAAGGUGCCUCCGUCCUGAGCUGCAUCAUCACACCCCUCUUGAACCCAUUCAUCUUCACUCUCCGCAAUGACAAGGUGCAGCAAGCACUGAGAGAAGCCUUGGGGUGGCCCAGGCUCACUGCUGUGAUGAAACUGAGGGUCACAAGUCAAAGGAAAUGA